ACUGCACUGCCGGGUGUUGGGAAUUCGGAGAGAAAUAUGAUGCUUAUUUUAGGCCUUUUUGUAUAUUUGUCCUAGCUCCUAGCCCAGUGUCAUGGAAACGGUAGGUAACCAGUAAACGUAAAACUAGGUCCUUCAUACAAUGGAUAAGUGUCUUGGCAACGUUGAUGGGGAAAAUUGUUGGAGAGAGCGCGGAGAGGUCAUCUUUAAGGAAGAUGAAGGGAUAUCUAGGUUUUUUUUCGGUUUUGUUUAAAGUACUGUCAAUUUCUGAAUACAUAGAGCUUUAAAUUUUUCGAUAGUGCAUUUCAACGCUCUUCAUAAAAUUUUAAAAGCCCACUGAAUACUACUUUGUAGCAAAUGAGAUAAUGUUAAGACCUACCCCUCUGAUGGGAGGUGGGGCGAGGACCGGAAUAUUAAGGAUCUUUAAAGGAAUCGACUUCAGCUCUGCAGAAAGAUUAGCAAUCAGUAAAGAUUUGGGGAUGAAUGGGCACCUAGAGAAGUUUAUUCUUGCUCUCUGUUAUUUCUGCUACUGGAUUUUAGAUCUUGUUAAUAUGGUAAUUCAGGUUUUGUCAGGAAUUGAUCCACACUUUUGAGUAACCUGGCUGCCACUUAAAAAGCUGUUACAUUGUUUUCCUCCUGAUCUUUAAAUGUGACUUGAUUGCUAGGAUAUCAGACACCUGUUUGGAAAUAUCUUUUAGCGUGACAGAAAACUCCAGGUGAUAUGAAAUUUAACAAAGUUAAAGGGAUUAAGUCAUUAAGUUUACAGCUUCGGAAGAGGUCGGUUUAAACUAGACGACCUUGAAGACCUUUCCCAAUCAUAUAAGCGUAUCUUUAAGUACCUGGGUUUUGUUUUUGUUUUGAGACAGGUGAGACAGGGUCUCUGUCGCCCAGGCUGGAGUGCAGUGGCACGAUCGAUCAGUGCUCCCUGCAGCCUCCACCUCCCUGGCUCAGGUGAUCCUCCUGCUUCAACCCCCUCUUCCCCCACCACCACUACAGUAGCUCGGACUACAGGUGUGCACCAUUACACCCGACUAAUUUUUUGUAUUUUUAGUAGAGACCAGAUUUUGCCACAUUGCCCAGGCUGGUCUCCAACUACUAGACCCAAGCGAUCUGCCCACCUCGGCCUCCCAAAGUGCUGGAAUUACAGGUGUGAGCCACCUCGCCCAGCCAGUACUUAAAAAAAAAAUUUUUUUAACCAUAAGUAAUGCAUUCAUUAAAAUACCUCCAAGCUGUUGCAGAAAAAAAAAAAAAAACUAGCAGGCCGGGCGCGGUGGCUCACUCCUGUAAUCCCAACACUUUGGGAGGCCAAGGCAGGCGGAUCACGAGGUCAGGAGAUCCAAACCAUCCUGGCUAACACAGUGAAACCCCGCCUCUACUAAAAAAAUACAAAAAAAUUAACCGGGCGUGGUAGCGGGCGCCUGUAGUCCCAGCUACUAGGGAGGCUGAGGCAGGAGAAUGGCGUGAACCCGGGAGGCGGAGCUUGCAGUGAGCCAAGAUGGCGCCACUGCACUCCAGCCUGGGCGACAGAGCGAGACUCUGUUUAAAAAAAAAAAAAAAAAAAUCUAGUUAUAAUAUAUAGUUGGGAAACAGUUUCUAAUGAGCAUCCACGGUAUGUGAGAGAUCAUUGAAGUUUUCUUAUGCCCAUUGACCUCACAUCUAAUUGAGGUAACAAAACAUUUUUUUACUAUUAAAAGUAGAUACUAAAUCACAAUACAACUCUAGAAAAACGCUAACAAUGUAGGAGUAAAUUCUAAGAGUCACCAGGUUAUGUAUUGAGGAGGUAAAUUGAUUGCAGUUCUGUAGUAAAGGGUAUUAAGGAUGAAAACAACUUAAAAGUCGUUUCAUUGGCUUGGAGUGGAGAAAUGAAAGCUAUCUUAUAGGAAGUGGGAAGAGUGGGGAGGUAAAUUUUAGUAACUGCUAAGGAACUCUCUUAAAAUGUAUAGUGCACCCACGUGCUUUUCAGAAUGCAGCAUUUGGGCAAGUACUCACUGUUGUACUUUAAGGCAGGGCUCUCCAACCCCUGGGCCACAGAACCAGGCUGCACAGCAGGACGUGAGCUGUGGGCCAGCCAGCAAAGCUUCAUCUGUAUUUACAGCCACUCCCCUUGGCUUGCAUUACCACCUGAGCUCUGCCUCCUGUUGGCAUUUGAUUCUUAUAAGAGCGUGAACCCUGGUGUGAACUGCACAUGCGAGUGAUCUAGGUUGCACACUCCUUAUGAGAAUCUAAUGCCAGAUGAUCUGUCAUUGUCUCCCAUUACCCCCCAGAUGGGACUGUCUAGUUUUAGGAAAACAAGCUCAAAGCUUCCAUUGAGUCUACAUUAUGGUGAGUUGUAUAAUUAUUUCAUUAUAGAUUACAGUGUAGUAAUAAUAGAAAUAAAGUGCCCAAUAAAUGUAAUGCACUUGAAUCAUCCUGAAACCAUCACAUCCUCCCUCUCAGUGGAAAAAUUGUCUUCCACGAAACUGGUCCCUGAUGCCAGUCUGGUCCUGGAGUGCUGCUUUAAGGUCUUUGAAAAGAAGAACUGGCAGGACUUAAUGUUAUUUCCUUAAAACAUUGGGAUUAGAAGUUGUAGAUGACAGUUAUUUAUAUAAACACUGAAAAUGUUUUUUAAUAGAAGCAGAAUCAAGAAAGUUGGUUUUUACACAAUUUUUUAACUUCUAUACAUUUUUAUAACUAGUUCAUAGACCACUUUCAUCUGUCUCAUUUGAUCAUGGACAGUAUGAUGUGGAAAAAACACAGGAUGGUCAGAGGAUCAAAGGAAGUCACUUAGCCUCUCUGUGCCUCAGUGUCUUAAGACAGUCUUUUAAAAAGGCAUCUCUUUAUAGAUAAGGAGUUAAAAUUAAGUUAAAUGUCAGAUCCUGGCUUACAGAGCAAGUGAUUUAGUGAUUGUCAGAACUGAAGCUUCACCAUUACUUUAACUAUAUUGAGCCAGAAAUAGUUAAGAACUAAAUGGCCCAUAAAAAUAUAUGAGGGGGGUCACAUGGAAAAAAGUAGAGAUUUGGAACUUAGGGAACCAAAAUUAUGAGAGCAUAUAAGCCCUUCCACUAAUGAGAAUUUAGAAGUGCAAAUGGGUCCAGGUUGGUACAAAUGCUUUAACUCUCAUAUGCCCAGGGGAAAUAGUGGUUUUUUUAAAUAUUCUUUUAGUCUUUUACAAAUAAUUUUUAGAAAUAAUAAUGGGAGAUAGUGCAAAACAACUUUAUUAGGAAUUUUAAUGUGAAUUUAACAAUAGCAAACCGAAAUUUAUAUUCUUUGUUUUCCUGAUUUUGAUGUACAUAUAGUCAUCCUUCAGUAUGCUAAAUGUGGGGGAUUGGUUCCAGGACCCACCCACCUCUUUGGCAAAUCUUGCAUACUCAAGUUCUGCAGCCAGCCCUGUGGAACCUGAGAAUAGGAAAAAUCAGCCUUCCAUAUACUUGGGAUGGAUCUGCAUUUGGUUGAAAAAAAUCCACUUAUAAGGGACCCUUGAAGUUCAAACCUGUCUCGGAUUUGCAUCAUCAAAAUACAAUACUUGAGGAAUUUUUGAAACCUAUUGCUUACAAUUUUGUAAUUGUCAUCCUUGCUCCAUAAUUGCAAAACAUUUUUAUUUUUAGAUUAUAAACUUAAUUAGAAUGAUAAAUUCGGUGAAUAUUUUUAUUUCAUUUUCCUUCCAGUCACCUUGUGUACACAUCUGCCUUCACCCUUUGUCCAUUUGCAACCAAAUCAAGUAAAUUUUGAUGCAUAAACAUUGUAAAAGAUGAGAUAAAACACUCACACCUCCUUUUAGAAAAUGGGAUGAUCCUGGCUCUUACUGUGAAAUAUUGCAAGAUGAAGUCCUUCCUGCUGAUGGCUCUCCCAGUGAGAGUACAUUUCUUGUUUGUCUUUUUUUUCUUUUUCUUGUCAAUUCUUGGGUGGGAGAAAAGCCUUCUAAUAUUUCCUCAUCCAAAAACUCAUAGUCUGAGAUUUUUGCAGUUAAUUUUAUCAUGAUUAGUCUAGAAUACGACUGCCUUUCAUUUUGCAUUCACCUUCUUCGUCUAAUAAUGAUUAAUGCCUUCUGUCAGUUUUUUCUCUUUGCCAUUAUGAAUGGAAAAUGAAAAAUUGUGAAUUCCCAUCGGUGUUCAGUGAAAGCUAAAAGUAGACAACAGCUGGGAUCUAGCAAUUGGGAGGCAGCAGACUUGGGUAAUGAAGAGAGAAAACAAAAGUUCUUGAGACUUAUGGGUGCAGGAAAGAAAGAACAUACUGGUCGUCUUGUUAUAGGAGAUCACAAAUCAACAUCUCACUUCCGAACCGGGGAAGAAGACAAGAAAAUUAAUGAAGAACUGGAGUCUCAAUAUCAGCAAAGUAUGGACAGUAAAUUAUCAGGAAGAUAUCGGCGACAUUGUGGACUUGGCUUCAGUGAGGUAGAAGACCAUGAUGGAGAAGGUGAUGUGGCUGGAGAUGAUGAUGAUGACGAUGAUGAUUCACCUGAUCCUGAAAGUCCAGAUGAUUCUGAAAGCGAUUCAGAGUCAGAGAAAGAAGAAUCUGCUGAAGAACUCCAAGCUGCUGAGCACCCUGAUGAAGUGGAGGAUCCCAAAAACAAAAAAGAUGCAAAAAGCAAUUAUAAAAUGAUGUUUGUUAAAUCCAGUGGUUCAUAACUCCCAAACGCUUAGUCUUUGUAUUAAAAGUAAGCCUUAUUGUUACAAUGCACAGUGGAGGACUGCUUAUAGAGCACAGACCUUUGUAUUAUAAUUUUUAAAAAGGCCCUUUUAAAUAAUUACAAAGAGUGUUUGCUUUCAAAUGCCAUGGGUUACACUUUUAUGGGCAUGACUAUAACCAUUUUUGUAAAGAGUAAGAGUUGUAUAAAAUAAGAAAUAAAUACAGUACUCAACUUCCUUUCAUAUUAGCAUCAUCAACCCUCUAAUUCACCUUAUGGGGGAAAUGCUUCUUUUUGUUUGUGAUAGCUAUUUUAUCAUUUCCUUCAUAUUUUUCUCUUAUAAAAAUGUAUUUGAUACUGUGAUAUGUUCACGAAAAGUAUUCUUUAAUUAUUCUUUGUUAUAGUAGAGCUGUUCAUUAUGGAUAUUUCUGCUGCCAGUCACAAUCUAAAUUAAUUUUGGCAAAAGAUUGGGUACUUAGUUUCCUGUUACUGAGUUAGCUCUACUCUUUUGGACCAAAGCAACAUGAGAGCAAGUACUUUUCACACUUGUUAAGAUGGAGUUAUAACUGUCAUACAUUUGGAAUAUUAUGAUCCCAAGUAGUCUUUUUAUAAUUUGGAUUGUAUCGUAUGUUAGAUUUUUGAUAAAAUUUGGCCAAUUUUUACAGAAGAAAUUCUCUGAUCAUUUAGUUCUGUCUAUUUAGAAAUAUGUAAAACUGGAUUUUUUUUUAAGUAAUAUGUGACCAAAGUUAAUUUUGUCCCAAAGGUCUAAAUAAAGAGCAGUUUCCCAUAUUUGGCUGUGAUACCUUUAUCCUCAUUAUCUACAAAUGAGGAACAGGCUUACUGAUAAGAAGCUGAAACAAGAAAUUCUCUUCAUUUUAUCCCAGUGCUAUUUUAUUGAUUAAUUACUAAAAAGUAUUACUUUCUAAUUUUAUUGCUGUUUCUGUUGGUGUGAGAUUAGAAUCAUCUGACUGCUAUUAGGUGGUUGAUUUGUAUAGCUGAUUAACACAAAUUGCAUUAUGAGCUAGUAAAUGGAUCUUUGGAUAAUGGGGUCCAAAUUCUUAAUGUUUAUAAGUAACAAGUUCAAAGGCUUUAGUCACACCUGUUUGUGAGCUGAGCUAUUAUACAUCUACAUACUUAAAGGAUGUAUUUGGAGUGUUGGAUUUUUUUUUUUUUUUUUUUUUUUUGAGACGGAGUCUCAUUCUGUCGCCCAGGCUGGAGUGCAGUGGCGCGAUCUCAGCUAACUGCAACCUCUGCCUCCCAGGUUCAAGCGAUUCUCCUGCCUCAGCCUCCCAAGUAGUUGGGACUACAGUCAUGUGCCACUACUCCUGGCUAAUUUUUUGUAUUUUUAGUAGAGUUGGGGUUUCACGGUGUUAGCCAGGAUCGUCUCGAUCUCCUGACCUCGUGAUCCACCCACCUUGGCCUCCCAAAGUGCUGGGAUUACAGGCGUGAGCCACCACGCCCAGCCUUGGAGUGUUGGAAUUUUUAAAAAUUAUUCUUAUGUCACUUUGAAAUGUAGAACGUGUUGCCAUGUGCGGUGGCUCACACCUAUAAUCCCAGCACUUUGGGAGGCCGAGGUGGCUGGAUCACCUGAAGUCAGGAGUUUGAGACCAGCCUGACCAACAUGGAGAAACCCCAUCUCUACUAAAAAUACAAAAUUAGCUGGGCGUGGUGGUGCAUGCCUGUAAUCCCAGCUACUCAGGAGGCUGAGGCAGGAGAAUCACUUGAACCCAGGAAGCGGAGGUUGCAGUGAGCCAAGAUCACCCCAUUGCACUCCAGCCUGGGCAACAAGAGCAAAACUCCAUCUCAAAAAAAAAAAAAAAAAAAAUUUAGAAUGUGUUAGAGAAAUUUAACAAGUAGAACAGGUGAUUUCUGGUUGAUAGACUCUAUCUUGCAGUAUAUUUAUUUCAUGUAUCAGACCCCAAAGUUGUUGCCUUGUUAUUUUUUUAAUUUCUCACAUUUUUGAAAAAUAGAUGCUAUCCUCUAUAGUAAAAUAUUGAAUCACUUUAUAGUAGACAAUACAUAUGACAUUUAACAAAUACUUGGUUUGAAAAAGUUUGGCUUUAUUCAACAAUUUUAGUUUGCCCACUGAUUUUCAAAUGUCUGUGGGAUUGCUUAUAACUAAGUAGAAAGUGAAGACUGAUUUUUACUUAAGAAUGGGAUAGAGAUGAGUUUUAUGGUUUUUAAAAGUAUUUUCAGUUCAUUAUUUAAAUGUUGGGUUGUUGAUAUGGUCUUGUUUCUGAUAAGGAAAUAGGAGCAACUUGUUUUAAAAUAACUACACUAAAAGACUUUCUUCAUCUCCGUAUAGAGAAAUCCAGAUUUCAAUUAAUUCAUUUAUUGGGUGCUAACAAAAUUCAGGGUUAGAGUAAAUUUAGGUCUGUUGGUCCAUGUGGCCUGGUUUCCUAGCACCCAUUAAACAUAAUGCUAUCUUUUAAGCCUGAACAUGUGGGUUUUUUAAAUCAAAUUGGAAAAAAAUUAGACAACUGAUGUCAUGCUGUCUUGGUAUCCAUACUAAAAAAGUAUCAGGAAAAUAGAUUAUUUUUGUGCUGUGAAACACUAUUCAGUGGAAAGUUUAGUGGCAACUUUUCCAUAUCAUUCAUGACUUAAUACCUGAAAUGCACUUUUAAAUGUUUGCCUUAUAUCCAAGUGUUUACUUGUAUCCAUGACCUAACCGUCUAUUGAAAAGAAUGUUUGCAGAUGCAGAUUGCAAUGUUGUUUGUAUUCAUAGGCAAAAGUCCUCUUCUCUAGUAUAAUUUUUUAAAUCUGAGAGAAUUGAAGGUACAGAAAAAAAUUCUGGAGUGCCUGAACCACAGUUUGAGAGCACAAAGGUCACAUUCUUUCAGUAAAUUUGGGGGAAAUAAAUUUCAGCUACCUGGUUAGCUUCAGUGACUACUUACACACAGGGCUUUGGUUCCAUUACUUGUUUCCACCACAGCCACAUCCUAAAUACUUGGAAUAUCCGAAAACAACUUCUAAAAUCACUCAAUAAAAGUAUUCACUUCUAACCAACUCCUCCUCCUUUAUACCUGCUCUGUGUUAGGGCGUAGUCUGUUUCCACCUCUGUAAGUCCUAUCUAGGCUUCCUGAUCUAUCAAUUCAGUAUCAUGAUUGUUAACCCAAACGACUUCCUGGAAAAUUCCCAGCCCUAGAUGUAUCCAAGCCCUCCUACCCUCACCAGUUAUUUCUGGAGAAAGAUCACCAAAUGUAUAAAUCCGUAUUAGUAAAAAUUGGUUUUAACUGA